GCCGCAGCAACCCAGAAAGCGUCAUGGCUGCCGCCGGCCAGGAAAAAGGGUAUUUGACACAGACUGCGGCAGCCCUAGACAAGUCACCGUCACUUUCGCCACAGCUAGCAGCUCCCAUCCGAGGGAGGCCUAAGAAGUGUCUGGUCUAUCCGCAUGCGCCGAAGAGCUCCCGCUUGUCUCGUUCCGUUCUGCGUUGGCUUCAGGGUCUGGAUCUCAGCUUCUUCCCCAGGAACAUCAACAGAGAUUUUUCAAAUGGCUUCCUAAUUGCAGAAAUAUUCUGUAUAUAUUACCCCUGGGAACUUGAAUUAUCAUCCUUUGAAAACGGGACCUCUUUAAAAGUCAAGUUGGAUAACUGGGCACAGUUGGAGAAGUUCCUGGCAAGAAAAAAAUUUAAAUUACCUAAAGAACUAAUCCAUGGAACAAUUCAUUGUAAAGCUGGAGUGCCUGAAAUAUUGAUAGAAGAGGUUUACACUUUAUUAACACAUCGAGAAAUUAAAAGUAUCCAGGAUGACUUUGUGAAUUUCACGGACUAUAGCUACCAGAUGCGUUUACCCCUGGUUUCCAGGUCUACAGUUUCGAAGUCUAUUAAAGAUAACAUUAGGUUAUCAGAAUUACUAAGCAAUCCCAACAUGCUGACCAAUGAACUUAAAGCGGAGUUCCUCAUCCUUUUACAUAUGUUGCAAAGAAAAUUAGGCAGAAAAUUGAAUCCAGAAUGGUUUGAUGUGAAACCAACAGUGGGAGAAGUUACUCUCAAUCACCUUCCUGCCCAAGCCUCUGGGCGCAGAUAUAAUUUAAAAGUUAAAAGAGGAAGAGUUGUCCCUGUUUUACCAAAUAUAGGUAGUGGUGGCAGUUCACAUAGAGAAAUACAUGUGAAGCAAGCUGGACAACAUUCUUAUUACUCUGCUAUGAAACCUAUCAGAAACAUGGACAAGAAACCUUGAAAAGCACCUGUCAAAUGGCUUUGAAGAAGUGAUGCCACCAUCUCUAGCCAUAAUAAAGAAACAGAAUCACCUAGUAUUGGAUGUAUUUCAAUAAUAAAUAGAGUGGUGUCUUUUCCAUAAUUGUGUUAAAGAACAUUUCUUUUCCAUUCAAUUUGUUUAUUAAACUCCUAUGCCAGGCAUUGUUGAAAAUACAAAAUUAAA